CUCUUCUUCCAGACUCUCGGUCUGUCCGCUGGGGGCGCGCGCGGUGUGUGGCAGGCGGCAGCGGCGCUGGCGGCCGAGUGCGCUUGUCACGCGUGGCGGUGCGUGGUUGCUAGGGGCGCCUGAGGCUGCCGGGUAGCCCAGCAGGCCGAGGGAGGAAGUAGCGUGGAGCCGGUGCCGAGCCGGGGCGAAGCUGGAUCCCCUAGAUAGACUGUCUUCAAGCUCACUGAUAUUUUCCUCUGCUUGAUCCAUUGUGCUGUUGAGAGCCUCUAGUAAAUUUUUCAGACUGACAGACUUCAAGGAUGCAGCUGCUACUACCGGAGGUGUGUGGCACCUUACCUCAGCAAGGCCAUGAGACCGUGUGGCCAUGAUGUGGGCCCCUCAUGGCCUCAGCAGGAACACAGCACUAUAGUAUUGGCCUCCGCCAGAAAAACAGCUUCAAGCAGAGUGGUCCCUCAGGCACAGUACCUGCCACGCCACCUGAGAAACCCUCGGAGGGCAGAGUCUGGCCUCAGGCCCAUCAGCAAGUGAAGCCAAUCUGGAAGCUGGAAAAGAAGCAAGUGGAGACACUGUCAGCAGGGUUGGGCCCAGGCCUCUUGGGCGUCCCACCCCAGCCAGCAUAUUUCUUUUGCCCCAGCACUUUAUGUAGCUCUGGGACCACGGCUGUCAUUGCAGGCCACAGCAGUUCCUGUUACCUACACUCUCUCCCGGACUUGUUCAACAGCACCCUGCUAUACCGCCGCUCCAGCUAUAGGCAAAAACCGUACCAGCAACUGGAGUCUUUCUGCUUGCGUUCGAGCCCGUCAGAAAAAAGCCCUUUUUCUCUCCCUCAAAAGAGCCUCCCUGUCAGUCUCACUGCCAACAAGGCCACUUCUUCCAUGGUCUUCUCCAUGGCCCAGCCCAUGGCCUCCUCAUCCACAGAACCAUACCUCUGCUUGGCAGCGGCUGGGGAAAACCCUUCAGGGAAGAGCCUGGCCUCUGCCAUCUCAGGGAAGAUCCCAUCUCCACUCUCUUCCUCCUAUAAGCCCAUGCUGAAUAAUAAUUCCUUCAUGUGGCCAAAUAGCACGCCAGUGCCUUUAUUGCAGACCACACAGGGCCUGAAGCCAGUAUCGCCACCCAAGAUCCAGCCUGUCUCCUGGCAUCAUUCAGGGGGUACUGGAGACUGUGCACCGCAGCCUGUUGACCAUAAGGUGCCCAAAAGCAUUGGCACUGUCCCAGCUGAUGCCAGUGCCCAUAUCGCCUUGUCUACCGCUAGCUCCCACGACACAUCCACCACCAGUGUUGCCUCUUCCUGGUAUAACCGGAAUAACUUAGCCAUGAGGGCAGAGCCACUUUCCUGUGCUCUGGAUGACAGCUCUGAUUCCCAGGAUCCAACUAAGGAGAUUCGGUUCACUGAGGCCGUGAGGAAAUUGACCGCAAGAGGCUUUGAGAAGAUGCCGAGGCAAGGCUGCCAGCUUGAACAGUCUAGUUUCCUGAACCCCAGCUUCCAGUGGAAUGUCCUCAACAGGAGCAGGCGGUGGAAACCUCCUGCGGUAAAUCAGCAGUUUCCUCAGGAGGAUGCUGGAUCGGUCAGGCGGGUCCUCCCUGGUGCCUCAGAUACCUUGGGGUUGGACAAUACAGUCUUCUGUACCAAGCGUAUCAGCAUUCACCUCCUUGCCUCACAUGCCAGUGGGCUCAAUCACAACCCUGCCUGUGAAUCUGUAAUUGACUCCUCAGCAUUUGGAGAAGGCAAAGCUCCAGGUCCCCCUUUUCCUCAAACUCUUGGCAUAGCCAACGUGGCCACCCGCCUCUCUUCCAUCCAGCUGGGCCAGUCUGAGAAGGAGAGACCUGAGGAGGCCAGGGAGCUGGACUCAUCUGAUAGGGAUAUUAGUUCAGCUACUGACCUCCAGCCAGAUCAGGCUGAGACUGAAGAUACAGAAGAAGAACUAGUAGAUGGUUUGGAAGACUGUUGUAGCCGUGAUGAGAAUGAAGAGGAGGAGGGAGACUCAGAGUGCUCCUCAUUAAGUGCUGUCUCCCCCAGCGAAUCGGUGGCCAUGAUCUCUAGAAGCUGUAUGGAAAUUCUGACCAAACCCCUUUCCAAUCAUGAGAAAGUUGUCCGACCAGCCCUCAUCUACAGUCUCUUUCCCAACGUUCCCCCUACCAUCUAUUUUGGCACUCGGGAUGAGAGAGUGGAGAAACUUCCCUGGGAACAGAGGAAGUUGCUCCGAUGGAAGAUGAGCACAGUGACCCCCAACAUUGUCAAGCAGACCAUUGGACGGUCCCACUUCAAAAUCAGCAAAAGAAACGAUGACUGGCUGGGCUGCUGGGGUCACCACAUGAAGUCUCCUAGUUUCCGAUCCAUUCGAGAGCAUCAGAAGCUAAACCAUUUCCCAGGCUCAUUCCAGAUUGGGAGGAAGGACCGGCUAUGGCGGAACCUGUCACGUAUGCAGAGCCGCUUUGGCAAGAAGGAGUUCAGUUUCUUCCCCCAGUCCUUUAUCCUGCCCCAGGACGCCAAGCUCCUGCGCAAAGCGUGGGAGAGCAGCAGCCGCCAAAAGUGGAUUGUGAAGCCACCAGCAUCAGCUCGAGGCAUUGGCAUCCAGGUUAUUCACAAGUGGAGUCAGCUCCCCAAGCGAAGGCCCCUCCUGGUACAGAGGUAUCUACACAAACCCUACCUCAUCAGCGGCAGCAAGUUUGACCUGCGGAUCUAUGUUUAUGUCACUUCCUACGAUCCUCUGCGGAUUUACCUCUUUUCAGAUGGACUGGUCCGCUUUGCCAGUUGCAAGUAUUCGCCUUCCAUGAAGAGCCUUGGCAAUAAGUUCAUGCACCUGACCAACUACAGUGUCAAUAAAAAGAAUGCCGAGUACCAGGCCAAUGCAGAUGAAAUGGCUUGCCAGGGCCACAAAUGGGCACUGAAGGCUUUGUGGAACUACCUGAGCCAGAAGGGAGUCAAUAGCGACGCCAUCUGGGAGAAGAUAAAGGAUGUUGUUGUCAAAACUAUCAUCUCGUCAGAGCCCUAUGUGACCAGCCUGCUCAAGAUGUAUGUGCGACGGCCCUAUAGCUGCCAUGAACUCUUUGGUUUUGACAUCAUGCUAGACGAAAACCUCAAGCCCUGGGUCCUGGAAGUCAACAUUUCCCCAAGCCUCCACUCCAGCUCUCCACUGGAUAUCAGCAUCAAAGGCCAGAUGAUUCGUGACCUUCUGAAUCUGGCAGGUUUUGUCCUGCCCAAUGCAGAGGAUAUCAUUUCCAGCCCCAGCAGCUGCAGCAGCUCCACCACCAGCCUGCCCACCUCCCCUGGGGACAAAUGUCGAAUGGCUCCAGAGCAUGUCACUGCACAGAAGAUGAAGAAAGCCUAUUAUCUGACCCAGAAAAUUCCUGAUCAGGACUUCUAUGCAUCUGUGCUGGAUGUCCUGACACCAGAUGAUGUUCGGAUUCUGGUUGAGAUGGAAGAUGAGUUUUCUCGCCGUGGUCAGUUUGAACGAAUUUUUCCUUCUCAUAUCUCCUCUCGCUAUCUCCGCUUUUUUGAGCAGCCACGAUAUUUCAACAUUCUCACCACCCAAUGGGAACAGAAAUACCAUGGCAACAAGCUUAAAGGAGUAGAUCUGCUCCGGAGUUGGUGCUACAAAGGGUUCCACAUGGGAGUUGUCUCUGAUUCUGCUCCAGUGGUGAGUGCUGCCAGUGUGGAGGACAGCUCCUUCUCAGGCCCCUCCCUCCUCUGCCUUAUGAGUGCAGCAGGAGUUGGGUUGUGGUCUCUCCCGACAUCACUUCUGACUAUCUCAAAGGAUGACGUGAUACUCAAUGCCUUCAGCAAAUCAGAGACUAGCAAGCUGGGAAACCCAGUUCCUCAAAGGACAGUGAGGACACCAGCAAAGAGCCCAGCCUUUCUACCCAGACGUUACCUGUGAUCAAGUGCUCUGGGCAGACUUCAAGACUUUCUGCUUCCUCCACUUUCCAGUCAAUCAGUGACUCCCUCCUGGCUGUGAGCCCAUAACUGGCCUCUCUCCAAAAGCCUCUGCCCAGGAGCAUGGGCAUCAGCUACCUCACGGGAACCAGCCUGCUGUUCAGACCAGUCUGACCCCCUACCCCUUUCACCCUGUCCCUCCUCAGAGUAUUUUUUGAAGUGGUUGCAUUAUAGAGAUGGGUAUUUGUAGGGCCGGAGGGAUGGUAGUGAUGGGGAGAAGGUGAGGAAGGGUCACCCUCUGUCACCUGUCUGCCUGGCUGGCACCUCAUAUCUCAGCAGAGAAGCCAGUGGUGGCCACGCAGCCUUAUAAAGCAGGUUUUGGUUUCUACCUUAAGUGAGCCAUGUGUGGUUUGUCUGGGGGCCCUGGUGUGGUUGCUGAGUUGUAGCUCAAGAGGAGAAAACAUACAGAACAUAUUUGGACCGGAAAUCCUUUGUUCUGAAUUUGAGGGGGUCUUCUGAGGUCCUUACUUCCUUAGGUCUUUCCUCACCCCUCUCCCACCGCUGUCCUGAGGAGAAACCCUUGAACUUCCUCAGUAGACAGGCGGAGAGGCCACAACAUGCCGAACCCAUUUCCUGUCAUCCUAGUCUUGGGUCUUCACCGCCUCCUUCCAAAUACCCACCCUGCCAGCAGCCCUAGGUCUUCCUGUUCUGACCCCCCAUCACUGCUCGUUCAGCCUUCUAGAUGUCUCUCUCGUGGACAUCUGUUCUUUAGCUGUUGGCUUUCUCUGAGGUGUGAGAGGGUCUAUGAACUUUGUGAAUUUCCCAUGGCCCCAGUGAAGGAGCCCAGAUAAUCCCAGUAGCUGUUACCUGUCUCCAUGUAUCAAAGGACACAGUCCAGGGGGAGGGUGGAAGGAGAUGUGGUUUCUCUAUAGUGCAACAAACAUGGUUUCUCAAUGUUCUGCUGUGCAGCAAGCAGGGUCUGGCGGCUUGGUAGGUGGGUUUCAGGAGCAGUCACUAUUGUAGGAUGGGCUUCCAAUCAAACCUCAGACUAAACUCUUGUACUGAACUGAUUCUACCUCCCUCCUCUAGACUCAGUAAACAGUGACUAUUCAAUAAAUGUUGACUGAGUGAACUGUAUUUACAGAGAUCUCAAAGGACCCCAGCACUUGAACCAGAAGUUCUAAUUGUCUCUCAUCUAGGUAUGAGAAAGUGGAACCUGGGAACAGCACAAGCGGAAGAGUUCGGAUCAGAAAGGUUUUCUCUGAAGCCGUGCUCCUUCCUAACCCUGCACUUAGUGGUUGCUGCUUGCCUCCUCCCCAGCCCCUGUAGUCCCUUUACUUAGUUUUUUCUAGCAGUGGCACAUAUAAGAAGCCAAUUGGCCCCGUGUCCCUGCUACUCAAGUUUUCUCUUUGCACAUCAGGCAGAAAGCUCAGCUACUUGGUCUCACCCUGGACUGUAGCUGCCCCCAUUCUCUCUGAGCUUUGGAAAGAUAGAGACUUCUGUGUUUCAUGGCUCCUGGAGUUCUGUGGCGAGGUGGGGUGGGGCCCUGGAAAGAUCACUGAGAGGCCUGAUUGGGUUCAAGGCCACAGAGUAGGUGGGUGUUUGGCCGGUCCUAAGGCCAUGUUGACAGUUGUGAAAGUUUGGUGACAAAGUCCUGGGCAUCAUUGGCUGCUCAAUAGUAAGGACUUUAAAGUCGGGCCAUAAUGGGAGAGGUCCUUGACACUCCUAUUGGAUCUUUUCUGAUGUAAUUGAAGUGACCCGCCUCUUCUCCCCGCUGGCUGCAGUAUUCUAGUGCAGACAUGACAUGGGGAAUCUGCUGCCUUCCUAAGAGAAAAUGAGCUGCCUGCCUGGCAGUUUUGUUGUGGCUGGGCCUUCACGGCAAGGACCUAGGCACGGAGUCCUGGUUGAGCUGGUUUACUCCAUGAAAACGAACUUCAGUUCUUUGGCUUGCCCCCUGAGAAUCCCUGUACAACACAACCAAUCUAUUUCCAUUGCCCUAACUGGAGAGGGAACCAGCAUUGCUGAAUGGGGGUAUUGGGGGAAGCAUGGUGGGGGAAGGGAGAAGGACUUAGGAAAUUAAGUCCUUGUGAGCAAUGAAGGUCCUAAAAGAGCAAUGGAAAGACACUGCUCUUAGUUUAAAACAAGUUUGUACAUUAUUCUUAAUUUUCAUCACAUUUGAGUAUCUGAUAGACAUGGGUGUUUUGCUGGGUAGGAGAAAGGAAUGGGACUUACAUACCACAUUUACCUCUCACUCUUGAGAGAAAAUUAAAUCUUAUCAAGCAUUUGGCAUAUAUACUUUUGUAUUGAAUGCCCACAAUAUGAGGUAUUCAGCUAAGCAGGAAUUUUUGAGAAGGAAUGAGAUUUUUUUGGGAAGGUUAAAUUGGGAGUAUAGUAGAAUAAAUAUUUGUCAGAAUAUGUCAGUUGUUUUCCUAAGUUGAUAACUUACCUAGUCUAUUUGGAGGAAGGGAGGCGAGUGUUCUUGAGACAAGGAAUGAAGUGCAGGCUAUUUCUGGAGUAGUGGAGUAAGGGCUUGGGGUGGAAAGUGGAGGAGGGCAGUCACUGCUGUUUACUUUGCAUCCACUUUGGAAUGAUGAGAAACUCAGUUUCUUAGAAGAAAUAGUAAUGAAGAGAUGGCCUUGUGUCAGGAAAGGAUCGGGAACCUUGAAUCAGGCUGACCUUGGGUUUAAAUCCCAGUUCUGCCACUUACUGUGUGACCUUGGGCAUGUCAUCUAACUUUUAAGUCUCCAUUUCUUUGUAGUAUGAAUAUAAUACCUACAGUGCAGGGUUGCGAAGAUUUAAACCAAAUGUAGUGAAAGUACGUAGGACAUAGAGGGCACUUUGCAUGGUCACACCUUCUCCACUUGCUGUCCAAGCCCUGUGCCCUAGGUGGGAAGAGACAGGCAAGAAACGUAAAACCCUCUCCUCCAGGAGGUGGAGCUGCCAUCGAGAUAUUUUAGAAGUGAAGAUGCCAGAACAGGGUCUAGAUAGCUCAUGGCCCUCACCUUCACCCCAGUGCACACACAAACAUCACCAUUCACCCUCCUAUUACAUUAUCACUCCUCUGGGGAUUUAUUCUUUGGUUAAACACUUCACAGUCAGAGCACAGAAUCCCUGAGAAAGGAAGCACAUUAAGCAUUAGAAGUAUGUGAACUGAGUGGGAUUAUUAAAUUAUUUCAAGAGAAGCUUUGAAAAGAAGGGGAAAGCAAGCACAGUGGGUGUCAGGUGGCUGGAAAGGGGAGAAGCAGGGUACAGAAAAUAAGAGAACUUGAUUGGAACUGGACCCAAAGAGCAGAUAUAUGGACCUAACAGCUGUACGAAGGGGCAGUUGUCAUUACAGGUACCUUCUCUUGGUUUCAAGCUGUUUGGCUGAGGGUGAGUAUCCCCCUGUCACCCUAGCCAAAGUACAUACCCAGUGGCUUCUGGGGCAGUCCAGUGCUGCUGAGGGCCAGUGAAGGAGACUGAUCAUCUGGACACAAAGACCUUUCUACUUCCUUCUCAGCUGAAUUAGUUACCCAAGAUAGGUGACCAACAAAGGCAGACAGGGAUCUCCUCUCCUGGGCUCCCCUUGAUUUGUCCUCUAAGAUUAAGGCUUACCUGUGACUGUUGUUCGAAUCCCCCAACUGCUGUGAGACUUGGAAACACUGAUGGUUUUCAGAUGGCUAAGAGAGCUCCAUUUCUUGCCACCUGAGAUUCUGACCAAGCCUUUCACAACCCUUCUUGGCCUUUUAGAGUUCCCCCUGUAGCAGAGUUUGCCCGCUCAUUAAUAUCCGGGGAUCUAUGCCAGCUCAUUUGGCUUGCCCCUUCACCAGCGUUGGAUCAGUGAAAGUUGCAAGCAGUCAUAUGUUGCUCUCGGCAAAUGUUUUACAGGUGAAAACACAAGAAGGGUCAAUAGCAGGUGGUGGUUUUCUAAAACCCAUCUGUGUCAUAAUUAUAAUAGACUGAGAUACAUGGAAUGCCAGGGACUGCCACAGGCAAAGCUAACAGAAUUUUGAAAAGAUAUUUAAGUUUCAGUUAGUAAACUGGGGACACCAAAGCCUACUCAGAAUAGUUAUGGGACUAAAAUAUGGAGGAAAAGCACCUAACAAGGUGCCUGAUAAUAUAUGAUGCAGAUUUAAAGUAGUGGAUUCUAAAACAGACCAAAACUACCACCCAGAACAUAUAAAGUAAAAGCACUAUAACAUGCAAUAGUGUUACAAUACUAUUACAAUAGCGUGUUAAUAUUACCAAACUAUGGUAAAAUAUACUUUGAUUUUAUCCAUAAUUAAAGCUGAGGAUGUAUUGAUAGUUAACUUAGAAAGAUUAAAGCCCCCAUCAUUAGCAGUCAGAGAAGAGCAGUUUAAACUGCAAGAUACCACUUAACACUAAAGUGGCUCAAACUUAAAAGAUUGAAAAUACCAAGUGUCAGUAUGAUACUGAGAUAUUGAGAAGGUGCUGAUGGGAAUGCAAAAUGAUGCACUGGAAAGCAGCUUGGUAGAUUCUUACAAAGUGAAACAUGUCCUUAACGUAUGACCUAGCAAUUCCACUCUUGCAGGCAAAUGUUCAUAGCAGCUUAUUCAUAGUAGCAAAAAUUUAGAAACAACCAUAUGUCCAACAAUCAGUGAAUUAACAAAUUGUGAUAUCUCUGUUCAGUGGAAUACCCUUAGAUAUAAAAAAGGAACAGAGGGCCGGGCGUGGUGGCUCACGCCUAUAAUCCCAGCACUUUGGGAGGCCAGGGCAGGUGGAUCACCUGAGGUCGGGAGUUUUGAGACCAGCCUGACCAACAUGGAGAAACGCCAUCUCUACUAAAAAUACAACAUUAGCUGGGCAUGGUGGUGCAUGCCUGUAAUCCCAGCUACUCGGGAGGCUGAGGCAGGACAAUCCCUUGAACCCAGGAGGCAGAAGGUUGCGGUGAGCCGAGAUCGCCCCAUUGCACUCCAGCCCGGGCAACAGGAGCAACACUCCGUCUCAAUAAAUAAAUAAAUAGGAAGAGUUCAGGUGCUGUGGCUCACGCCUGUAAUCCCAGCACUUUGGGAGGCCAAGGCAGGAGGAUCACUUGAGCCCAGGAGUUCGAGACCAGCCUGGGCCAACACAGUGGGACCCUGUUUCUACAAAACAAAUAAAUAGAAAUAAAAAAGGAAUAAAUUGGUUCAUGCAACACCAUGGAUGAAGCUAAGCGAGAACAAGCCAGAAACAAAAGACUGCAUGCUUUGUUAUUCCAUAAUGGUCUAGAAAAUGCAAACUAUAGUCACAGAAAGCAGAACAGUGCUUGCCAGGGACUAUAGAUGAGGGAGGGGUAGACUGUAGAGGGCAUGGUGGGAAGAUUCUGUAUCUUGACUGUGGUGGUGGAUACAUGACUAUAUACAGUUGUGGGAACUUGUCAAAUUGUGCACUUAAAAUGGGUGAGUAGUAUUGUAUGUAAGUAAAUAAAGCUGAUUUAAAAGAAAAA